AGCAGCCGCCGCCCGCGACCUCCUCUCCUCCUCCGUCGUCACCCCGGCCGCCCUGCCAGCCCCGAACUUGCCCGCGCCUGGCCGCGCGGCCCCUCAGCCCACGGGGCUGGCGGCGCGGUUGGGAUGGGACCGAUGUGGCGCAUGCGUGGUGGCGCCACUAGGCGCGGGAGUUGCUGCGGCGGGGACGGUGCUGCGGACGGCCGAGGGCCAGGCCGCUCCGGCCGGGCUCGUGGUGGGGGCAGCCCCAGCGGCGGCGGCGGCGGCGUGGGCUGGCGAGGCCGCGCGGACGGCGCCCGACAGCAGCUGGAGGAGCGGUUUGCCGACCUGGCGGCGAGCCACUUGGAGGCCAUCCGUGCGCGGGACGAGUGGGACCGGCAGAACGCGCGGCUGCGUCAGGAGAACGCCCGGCUGCGGCUCGAGAACCGGCGGCUGAAGCGCGAGAACCGCAGCCUCUUCCGUCAGGCUUUGCGGCUCCCCGGCGAAGGCGGCAACGGGACGCCCGCGGAGGCACGCCGGGUCCCUGAAGAGGCCAGCACGAACCGGAGGGCUAGAGACAGCGGCCGAGAGGACGAGCCGGGCAGCCCCAGGGCCCUGAGGGCCCGACUUGAGAAGCUGGAAGCCAUGUACCGCCGGGCCCUGCUGCAGCUGCACCUCGAGCAGCGGGGACCACGUCCGAGCGGGGACAAGGAGGAGCAGCCUCUACAGGAACCCGACUCCGGCCUCCGCUCCCGGGACUCGGAGCCCUCUGGGCCCUGGCUGUAGCCGAGGCCGCAGCCGGUGAGAGGCGGAGCCUCGAGCGGGCCCCUCCUCCUCCGUUCCCAGCUACCCCCGACCUCGCGCACGCCCUGGCCCGCUCCCUGCCCGCGGAUACCUUGGACUACGGUGCCUUCCCGCCCCCACCAGUGGACACUUCCGGGUGGCGCUUGGCCAUCCGCUUGGUGGAGGUCGAGUGGGUGCAAGGGCCCUCAGGACCUCCCACAUGUACAGUUCCCCUGCCUCUUGCCCCGGCUAGUUUCCCUGGAGAGAGGCCUAGCCAACAACGAAGGGACGGAUUUUAAAACAGCGAGAACUGGGUGCCAAGAAACACUUCAUAUUCCCUGAACUUUUCUGGAUGUUGUGCGAACCUGUUGUAUUUUUUUUUUUCCUGUAUUUUGGUUCUGAGGGAUGAGUAAUGUGUUUUUAGUUGGUUGAGUUUAUCCAUUCUUCAAUCCCCUAAAGCCUUCAGCUAUUCUUUCAUAUGUGGCCAACAUUUUAAGUACAGUGUUUGCUUUUAUAAGUCGGUGUUACUUGGAUGUCCUAUAAAAUACCCACUUUUUAUAAAGAUGAUAUUUAUAACCUAGGAACUCAUGCCUGUCUUGGCUGCAGUCCCUGUACAUCUAAUAUAUACUGAUUUGUUUGCCCCCAGAGAAUUUUUAAGGUAUCUGCCUAUAUCGUGAUCUUUUGAAAUGGUAAAUAAAUCUGGUGCAUUAAAAAUUA